GUAAAGCUAGGCCUGCUGGGAGAGGAUGAGGAGGAGGCCCUGCCCCUCCAAACGUGGCCUCCUAUGGACACCCAGACUCACAGCCUUCCUAUCACCCACACUCAGCUCCAUAGCAACUCUCAGCCCCAAAGCCGCACCUGCACCCGCCAUUGCCAAACCUUCAGCCAGAGUUGCAGACAGAGCCAUCGUGGCAGCCGGAGCCAGAGCUCCAGCCAGAGCCCGGCCAGCCACCGCAACCCAACUGGAGCCCACAGCUCAUCCGGCCACCAGAGCCAGAGUCCCAACACUAGUCCACCACCAAAGCGCCACAAAAAGACUAUGAACUCCCACCACUCUCCCAUGCGGCCCACCAUCCUGCACUGCCGCUGCCCCAAGAACAGAAAGAACUUGGAAGGCAAGCUGAAAAAGAAAAAAAUGGCCAAGAGGAUCCAGCAGGUGUACAAAACCAAGACGCGGAGCUCAGGAUGGAAAUCCAACUAAUGAGACCGCACUCCUUGGCUUGUUCCUGCGUGUUUCACCCAAAGGAGAAAAUGCUAGGAUGAAGUCAAUCUUCUUGCAGGAACAUGUUACUAUGGUGAUUUCUACGCAACACUAAUUAAAGCUUGUACCUGGAAGACUA